UCAAAAAAAAAAAAGGUAAACUAAGGGCUUGCUCCCUGAGAAUAGACACUGUCUCCCUUCCCUUGAGACUCCCCUACACCCCAAGUCAAGAACUCUUGAGAAAGAAUAGGCAUAUGAACAGGCUCUCCCAGAAUGGGAAGUUCUGGAUACCACGUACCCAUGAGCUCCCCACACCAGAAUCUUCUUCCUUGUCCCUGCUCUAAUUUUUUCCAUAGAACUUAACAUCUUCUAGCAUACAUUAUAAUUUACUUAUUUUCCAUAUUUAGUGUUUAUUUUUGUCUGUCUCUACCCACCUCCCCCACUAGAAGAUAAGCUUCAGAGGGCUGGAGUUAUUGUUUGGUUCACUGCUGGAUUCCAAAUGCCUAAAAUAGUAUCUGGCACACAGUAGGUGUUCAAGAAAUAUUUGUUGAAGGAACAAAUGCUAAAAGGAAGGGAUCGAUGGAAAAAAACUUCCCUGGGUCAGGCCCAGCUUCCUGCCUUGUUACCUGGUUUCUCCUCAAACAAACAGAGGUGGGUGGGGAGUGUCCCUGAGCACCCAGCCUGCAGGCUUUCAGACUGGGUCCAGGCUGGGCUGUGGGUGAGAGGGUGCAGUGCUCAGCCUGGCAGUUGGUCUCUCAGUGGCCAUGGCAUUCAGGGGGCCUGAACCCUGGGUCUCUGCAUCCCUGCUGAGACAGAGGCUGAAGGCCGAGGAGAAGACGCUGGAUCUGGAGUUCGAAGUUUUGAGCGUGGGGUUUAAUGAGGCGGGUAGAUACGCCCUGAGACUGUCAGCAGAGAACCCCCUGCAGGUGGGCUCUGGGGCUGGGGUGCAGUUGCAAGUGAAUGAUGGGGACCCCUUCCCUGCCUGCUCUGCUAUCACUGAUGUCAUUGAGCAGCAGGAGCCUGGCCAGAGCCUCACCCUCACCAGGAGCAAGUUUAUCUUUACUUUGCCCAAAGGUUUCUGCAAGAAUGACGGGCAGCAUGAUGCUCAGCUGCAUGUGGAGGCACUGAGGCUGGACGAACCCUUGGGACGGGCAGCCCAGCGGGUGGGUGAGGCCAUCUUCCCCAUCUACCCGAGGCCAGACCAACCCCGCAUGAACCCAAAGGCUCAGGAUCACGAGGACCUGUACCGCUACUGUGGCAACCUGGCUCUGCUCCGGGCUAGCACGGACCCCACAGCCCGACACUGUGGGAGCCUGGCCUACAGUGUGGCCUUCCACGUCCACCGGGGCCCUCAGCCUCCAGUCUCAGACAGCCCUCCCAGGGCUGGCCAGCCAGAACUGAUGUCACCAUGCCCAGAGCCCCAGCUCCCCAUACUGCAGAACACUGAAGACCCAGAGGAGCCCCUGAUCGCCUCCCAGAGCACGGAACCUGAGAUCGGUCACCUGUCUCCCUCUAAGAAGGAGACCAUCAUGGUCACCCUCCAUGGGGCUACCAACCUGCCUGCCUGCAAGGAUGGCUCCGAGCCGUGGCCCUAUGUGGUGGUGAAAAGCACAUCUGAGGAAAAGAACAAUCAGAGCUCCAAGGCAGUCACAUCUGUGACCUCAGAGCCCACCAGAGCCCCUAUCUGGGGGGACACGGUGAAUGUGGAGAUCCAAGCUGAGGAUGCAGGGCAAGAAGAUGUGAUCCUCAAGGUGGUGGACAACAGAAAGAAACAGGAGUUGUUGUCCUACAAAAUCCCCAUCAAGUACCUGCGUGUCUUCCACCCCUACCACUUUGAGCUGGUGAAGCCCACUGAGUCUGGGAAAGCCGAUGAAGCCACUGCCAAGACCCAGUUGUACGCAACAGUCGUUCGGAAGAGCAGCUUCAUACCCCGCUACAUCGGCUGCAACCACAUGGCUCUGGAGAUCUUUCUCCGGGGAGUCAACGAGCCCCUGGCCAACAACCCCAACCCCAUAGUGGUGAUUGCCCGGGUCGUUCCCAACUACAAGGAAUUUAAGGUCAGCCAGGCUAACAGGGACCUGGCCUCUGUGGGGCUGCCCAUCACCCCACUGUCCUUCCCUAUCCCGUCCAUGAUGAACUUUGACGUGCCUCGCGUCAGCCAGAACGGAUGCCCUCAGCUGUCCAAGCCUGGGGGACCCCCAGAGCAGCCCCUGUGGAAUCAGUCCUUCCUCUUCCAAGGCCGAGAUGGAGCUACCAGCUUCUCAGAAGACACAGCCCUGGUGCUGGAGUACUACUCCUCAACUUCAAUGAAAGGCAGCCAGCCGUGGACCCUCAACCAGCCCCUGGGCAUCUCUGUGUUGCCGCUAAAGAGCCGUUUGUACCAGAAGAUGCUGACAGGGAAAGGCUUGGACGGGCUUCACGUGGAGCGGCUCCCCAUCAUGGACACCAGCCUGAAAACUAUCAAUGAUGAGGCCCCCACAGUGGCUCUCUCCUUCCAGCUGCUUUCCUCUGAGAGACCAGAAAACUUCUUGACACCAAACAACAGCAAGGCUCUUCCUACCUUGGACCCCAAGAUCCUGGAUAAGAAGCUGAGAACCAUCCAAGAGUCCUGGUCCAAGGACACAGUGAGCUCCACAAUGGACUUGAGCACGUCCACUCCACGAGAAGCAGAGGAGGAACCUCUGGUGCCUGAGAUGUCCCAUGACACAGAGAUGAACAACUACCGGCGGGCCAUGCAGAAGAUGGCAGAGGACAUCCUGUCUCUGCGGAGACAGGCCAGCAUCCUGGAAGGAGAGAACCGCAUACUGAGGAGCCGCCUGGCCCAGCAGGAGGAGGAAGAGGGGCAGGGCAAAGCCAGUGAGGCCCAGAACACGGUGUCCAUGAAGCAGAAACUGCUGCUGAGUGAGCUGGAUAUGAAGAAACUGAGGGACAGGGUGCAGCAUUUGCAGAAUGAGCUGAUUCGAAAGAAUGAUCGAGAGAAGGAGCUGCUCCUUCUGUAUCAGGCCCAGCAGCCACAGGCCGCUCUGCUGAAGCAGUACCAGGGCAAGCUGCAGAAGAUGAAGGCGCUGGAGGAGACUGUGCGGCACCAAGAGAAGGUGAUCGAGAAGAUGGAGCGGGUGCUGGAGGACAGGCUGCAGGACAGGAGCAAGCCCCCUCCUCUGAACAGGCAGCAGGGAAAGCCCUACACGGGCUUCCCUAUGCUCUCAGCCUCUGGCCUUCCCUUGGGUUCUAUGGGAGAGAACCUGCCGGUUGAACUUUACUCGGUGCUGCUGGCAGAAAACGCGAAGCUGCGGACGGAGCUGGAUAAGAACCGCCACCAGCAGGCCCCCAUCAUUCUGCAGCAACAGGCCCUGCCGGUGGACCCCGGGGAGUUGGGAGCAGGAGGAGACUUGACAGAGAGGCUACAAGAGACGCAUGGCCCAGGCCACUCAGAGUGCACAGAGACCCUGCCCGCACAGGAUCUCCUCUCUGGUACUUCAGACAAGUUCAACCUCCUGGCCAAGCUGGAACACGCUCAGAGCCGGAUCCUGUCCCUGGAAAGCCAGUUAGAGGACUCAGCUCGACGCUGGGGACGAGAGAAGCAGGAUCUGGCCACACGGCUGCAGGAGCAAGAAAAAGGUUUCAGGCACCCCUCGAACUCCAUCAUCAUAGAACAGCCUGUGAGUGACCCCCCUGGAGUAGCUCCCAGGGGUUCAGGUGGUGGAGCAGGAAGCCACCGCACCCCCAAAGUCACUGGGCCCUGAGAAAAGCCAUUGUGGAGCCAACUCCAGGGCUGGGGGUCAGGAGUCCUAGGCUCCCAUUCCUGCUCCAUUACCAACCGAAGGCUCGGUCUUAAUUCCCCCACCUGUCUAAGGGGAACAGAAAACCCCUGCCAAAACUACCCUUUCCCCCAUGGGGUGCUGUGAAACUCAAGGAGAUGACUGUGGAUGAGGGGUCCAUGCAGGCAUCUCCAGGAUGCCCUGACACUGUGCUUUAGGACUGGCUGCGCUCAUGGGCAGAGUAGCUUGUGGCCCUACCCCCCUGAAUCCAUAGAGCCUAAGAUUCUCAAAUUAGCACACCCUUCUCAGAUGGCCACGAUGUAGGCUCCACUUUGCCAACUUCCCGAGAACAAACAGGCCUGCUCACAACUGCCCCUCAAGUUCAACCCCGGGACCGCCCAGCCCCGCAAAGCAAAGACCCUGACUUCUCCUGCUCUUGAGCCAGCUGUGCUUUGCCCGUGGCCAGAAGCUCAGCAGCGGCUCCUGGGAAAGGCCUGGAAAGGAUGAGGGAACAGGCAAGGAACAAAGGCAACCUUUGCACACUCACCUGAGCCCUGGGGACCCUUGGAGAAAUUAGGUGUCACCUGCUGUGGCAAAAUGGGUUUAGAAAUCUUUGCCAGGUCAUGGCCCACUGGAUUCUGGAUACUCUGAGGCCUGGUUUGUCAGGCAAUAUGCCCUUGAGCAGGUCACCCCCUGGGAAUGGGGGGUACUCACGCACCCCGCUUUGCACACCACAGAGUGCCCUCACCCACUCCAUGGACCUCAAGCAGCCCUCAGAGCUGGAGCCCCUGCUGCCCAGCUCAGACUCUAAGCUCAACAAGCCCUUGAGCCCCCAGAAGGAGACCGCUAACUCUCAGCAGACCUGAGCCCCAGAGCAGGCCUCCUUCCCUGUGUGCUGGGGAGUCUCAUCACCGCCCCCUAAAAAUGACGUUAUUAAAUGUUGUAGCUCUGUGA